CUUGACGUCCGGAGCCCCUGGAGUAGGCGCUUCCGGCCAUUCAUACUGCAGUCGGUCAGUGUUCGGUUGAAGGAUUCUGUGUGCUGUCGGACCCAGAGGGUGACGGCGCCGCUAGGAUGAAGCUCGUGAGAUUUUUGAUGAAAUUGAGUCAUGAAACUGUAACCAUUGAAUUGAAGAACGGAACACAGGUCCAUGGAACAAUCACAGGUGUGGAUGUCAGCAUGAAUACACAUCUUAAAGCUGUGAAAAUGACCCUGAAGAACAGAGAACCUGUACAGCUGGAAACGCUGAGUAUUCGAGGAAAUAACAUUCGGUAUUUUAUUCUACCAGACAGUUUACCUCUGGAUACACUACUUGUGGAUGUUGAACCUAAGGUGAAAUCUAAGAAAAGGGAAGCUGUUGCAGGAAGAGGCAGAGGAAGAGGAAGAGGAAGAGGACGUGGCCGUGGCAGAGGAAGAGGGGGUCCUAGGCGAUAAUGUCUCUCAAGAUUUCAAAGUCAUAUGAGAUUUGGGAUAUUUUUUGUACAGGUUGUGUUUGUUUAUGUCAGUUUUUAAUAAACAUAAAUGUGGGACAGAGCUGUCUAUUUAGUAUAUCAAAGUUUUAGUAGUUUCCUCCACAUUCACGAAAUUACCACAGUGAGAGCUAAGCAUUUCUACUGGGCAGUUUCAUUUUUAGUUGAUCAGGUUUUAAGUUUUUGAACUAAAAUUUUUCUUUUUCUUUUUAUGAUGAAUAAGGUUAAAAUAAAAGCCUUAGACAAAUUAAAUUUGGCAGAGUUUAAUUGAGCAAAGGACAAUUCACAAAUCAGGUAGCCCCUGAACCAUAAUAGGCUCAGAGGCUUCAGCCCAGCUGCAUAGUUGAAGAUUUAUGGACAGAAGGAAAGUGAUGUAUGGAAAAUGGAAGUGAGAUACAGCAACAGCCGGAUUAGUUACAGUUCAGCGUUUGCCUUAUUUGAAUAUGGUUUGAACAGUUCGCUGUCUUUGGUUGGCUGAAACUUAGUGAUUGCCACAAGAGUAGGGUACCGUCUGUUUACACGUCCAGUUAGGCUACAGUUCUAUGUACUGAGAAACCUUUAAGCUGAACUUGAGAUAUGUAAAGAGACUUUAGGCUAAACUUAACAAUAUAUAUAGGAUAUAUACCCUUCUACUUCACAUGCACUGAAUAUGCAUUUUAUUGCUUUACUCUUCAUUCUGUGGCACCUACCCACAGGGGAAGUAAGAAGUUUGUUUUGGUAUUUCGGAAACUAAAGUCCUUAUGGGAUGGGGUCUAGAAUUGAUUCUCCUUUCCUGAGUUUUACUCCACGGAGUCUUAGGUACCUGGUAAAAAGUUGUCUUCUAAAUUAAGGGUCAUUGCUUUGUUGUCUAGCUGCUAAUGUCUUACUUUUGUUUCUUUUGCUUUUUAAUCAGUUCUUAAUAGGAUAUAGUUUUAUGUUUUCCAAGUUAUAACUUGGAGUUAAUGGUCACUAGAUUAUCAGUUAUGAGCAGUGUUAAAAUCUCCUAUUAAUGUGUAAUGUACCUGUCAGUGCCUCCUUUAUUAAGGGGUUCUUUGAGAAUAAAAGAGAAAAGACCUACUUUAUUUGACAGCAAAACUGUUCUAAUUGUUAAUAAGGACUUUUAAAAAUUGUUUUUGAUUUGCUAAGCUCAGAAAAAAUGUCUCUCAGUGCAUCAGUUCUUUGUAAAGCUUACUACGAAGUAUUUAUAUGCUAAGGAAAACAACUGAGGAUGUGGGUGGCUUAAAUCUGUAUUUUCAUCAUGUAUGUGAGUUUUUUUUUUUUUAAGUAAAGAAAUUUUCUGCAAAGAUCGUUACCUUAAAAAAGUUUAGCCUGGGUGUGGUGGCUCACGCCUGUAAUCCCAGCACUUUGGGAGGCCGAGGCAGGUGGAUCACGAGGUCAGGAGUUGAAGACCAGCUUGGCCAAGAGGGUGAAACCCCAUUUCUACUAAAAAUACAAAAGUUAGCCAGGUGCAGUGACAGGCGCCUGUAAUCCCAGCUACUCAUGAGGCCGAGGCAGGAGAAUUGCUUGAACCCAGGAGGCGGAGGUUGCAGUGAGCCGAGAUUGUGCCACUGCACUCCAGCCUGGGCGAUGGAGUGAGACUACGUCUCAAAAAAAAAUCGAGAGAGAGAUAUAUAUAUGUAUUUAUAUAUAUAUGUAUUUAUACUAAUAUAUAAAUAUAUACUAAUAGAUAUAUUAGUAUACAUGUAGAAUGUACCUGUCAUAUAUAUUAGAUAUAUAAAUGUAUAUAUUGGUAUAAAUAAAUACUAGAUAUAUAUUUUUUUAAGUAUCUUACCUCAUCAAGUAAAUUCAAAUGCUUUUUGAUUUUUCCACAGUUGAUAAUUUUUUUUUGUAAGUCAUUGAAGUUAUAUAGUAAUUAGCGUUUUUUCCCCCACAAAUUAUUGGCAGUGGUCACCCAGUUGUAUUACAGGUUCUAUGAUCCAAAAAGGGAUGUAUGAAAUUCAUGAUGAUUAAGACAAUUUUUUCUUUCUUUCUUUUGAGACAGAGUCUUGCUGUGUCACCCAGGCUGGAGUGCAGUGGUGCGAUCUUGGCUCACUGCAACCUCUGCGUCCCGGGUUCAAGAGAUUAUUGUGCCUCAGCCUCCAGAGUAGCUGGGAUUAUAAGCGUGCGCCACCACACCCAGCUAAUUUUUUUGUAUUUUUAGUAGAGACGGGGUUUCACCAUGUUGGCCAGACUUAAGACAAUUCUUUAAUAGUAAAUAUAUUAAAGGUGAGUUGGCUUGACAAGAUACAACCAAUAUGUAAUUUUUCUCCACACGUUUUUUUUUUUUUUUUUUUUUUUUUUCUGGAGACAGUCUUGCUCUGUUGCCCAGGCUGGAGUACAGUGGCGCGAUCUUGGCUCACUGCAAGCUCUGCCUCCCGGGUUCAGGCCAUUCUCCUGCCUCAGCCUCCCGAGUAGCUGGGACUACAGGUGCCUGCCACCACACCCAGCUAAUUUUUUGUCUUUUUAGUAGAGACGGGGUUUCACUGUGUUAGGAUGGUCUCGUUCUCCUGACCUCAUGAUCUGCACGAGGCCUCCCAAUGUGCUGGGAUUACAGGCGUGAGCCACCGUGCGUCCCCGGCCUAUACCUUUCAUUAAUUAAUAAGCUGGGGGAAUAAAUAACUGGAUUUCAUUCUUUUCCAUCUUCUGACCUGUUGGUGCUCCUAUUGCUUGUAUCCAAGUAGAAGGCAAAAGGCAAGAGACCCCUGUAAUGCAGCAAGUGGAGAGAUUUGUUGAAGGGGUCAAACAAAACCCUGCAAGAGUAGGAAAUAAACAGUUGGCUCCUGUCCUCGUGGAGCUUAUAGACAGAAGCAGAUAACAAAUAAAAAUUGGAGCUUAGUGCCGUGGUGCACACUUGUAGUCCCUGCUACUGGGGAGGCUAAGGCAAGAGGAUCGCUAUAGCCUGGGAAUUUGAAGCUGUAGCGUGCUAUGAUUGCAAGCAGCCUGGGUAACCUAGUGAGACCUGGCUCUUAAAUUUAAAAUUUAAAUGAAAAUGGCCACUUAGCAUAAGAGAUCUAAAAUUACGUUUUGUCCUGGCAUGGUGGCUCAUGCCUGUGACCUCAGCACUUUGGGAGGCCGAGAUGGGCGAAUCACUUGAGGUCAGGAGUUCGAGACCAGCCUGGGUAACAUGGUGAAACCCUGUCUACUGAAAAUACAAAAAUUAGCUUGGUGUGGUGGCGGGUGCCUGUAAUCUCAGUUACUCAGGAGGCUUAGGCAGGAGAAUCACUUGAACCCUGGAGGCAGAGGUUGCAGUGAGCUGAGAUCACACCACUGCACUUCAGCCUGAGUGACAGAGCGAGACUGUUUCAAAAAAAAAAAAAAAAUUUGUUUUGAGAGUUUUUGUGUCUAGGAUGUUUGCAGUGUGAAGCCAGUCUAGUAACAGUUUAAAUGUAAUAAUAAAUCACAGUGGGUACUAGAUUGAGUUUAUUCCACUAGAGGUCAUUAUUUCAUUUCCAUGUGAAAGGGCUAAAAUUGGGUGAAGAAAAAGCUAUUUGAACUGAUUACCAUCAUUUGCUAUAAAGGAAGCAUUAUAGUAUGAAUAGAAAACAGACUAGAGUUUAACAUGCUUCUCUUGACCCCUCUUCACCACCCCCUAAAAGGCAGAUGGGAUCUUAGGACUGCAGCAUUUUGUACACAUCUGAUAUUUAAUGAGAUGUUACAUAUGAACUUUAGUUUUUUUUCUUUUCUUUUCUUUUCUUUUCUUUUCUUUUUUUUUUUUUGAGACAGAGUCUAGCUCUGUCACCCAGGCUGGAGUGCAGUGGUGCAAUCUCGGCUCACUGCAAACUCUGCCUCCCGGGUUCACGCCAUUCUCCUGCCUCAGCCUCCUGAGUAGCUGAGACUACAGGUGCCCACCACUAUGCCCGGCUAAUGUUUUGUACUUUUAGUAGAGACGGGGUUUCACUGUGUUAGCCAGGAUGGUCUGAAUCUCCUGACCUCGUGAUUCGCCCGCCUCGGCCUCCCAAAGUGCUGGGAUUACAGGCGUGAGCCACCGCGUCCGGCCGAACAUUAGUUUUUAAAGAAAUGUAUUAUGAAUAUAGAUAGAAAACCCAAAGUGAAGGAAUAGAAAAUGAAAUAUCAGUUUCUUUUAAUCUAUCAUAAUUAUGUGAGCAUAACUUAGUAUUUUGAAAUAGAUUAAUGUAGUCAGCAAACAAUUCAUGUAUUACCUAUAAUAGAUAUCAUACAUAUAACAUUUAAUAACAUACAGUUCUUGUUCCUGAAGACUUAACCUAGAAAAUAACUCCAUAACAAGAAGAAUCUCUGUCAUAAUAAACCAACAGCAGACAUUUUCUAAAGGCAUUAAAAGUAUAUCUGAUACUGGCCUUUAUUAAUGUGAAAUUCUUGUGGAUCUGUGAAAUAAAGAGGAGUACUUUC